ACUUCCGACUCAGCCCUCGGUUCAGGUUCCGGGGCGCCGCAGAGCUCCCGGCCUCUGGACCGCGCGCGGCGCUCUGGGGAAUCCGGCGCCACGCGCCGUGCGGUGGCCAGGAUGGAGGAGGCCGGAGCAGCGGUGGUCACGGCCGGGGAGGCCGAACUGAACUGGUCCCGCCUCAGCGUGUCCACCGAGACGCUGGAGUCUGAGCUGGAGGCGCGGGGGGAGGAGCGGCGCGGGGCGCGGGAGGCGCUGCUGCGGCUGCUGCUGCCUCACAACCGUCUGGUGUCGCUGCCACGGGCGCUGGGCAGCGGCUUCCCGCACCUCCAGCUGCUGGACGUGAGCGGCAACGCGUUGACCGCGCUCGGGCCGGAGCUGCUCGCUCUGCGCGGCCUGCGCACGCUGCUGGCCAAGAACAACCGGCUCGGCGGGCCCAGUGCGCUGCCCAAGGGCCUGGCCCAGUCGCCGCUCUGCCGCAGCCUCCAGGUGCUCAACCUCAGCGGCAACUGUUUCCAGGAGGUGCCUGCCUCGCUCUUAGAGCUGCGCGCGCUGCAGACCCUGAGCCUGGGCGGCAACCAACUGCAGAGCAUCCCGGCUGAGAUCGAGAACUUGCAGAGUUUAGAGUGUUUAUAUCUUGGAGGAAAUUUCAUUAAAGAAAUCCCACCAGAAUUAGGAAAUCUGCCUUCUCUGAAUUAUUUGGUAUUAUGUGACAACAAAAUCCAAAGCAUACCUCCUCAACUUUCACAGUUACAUUCACUUCGUUCCCUAAGUCUUCACAAUAACUUGCUGACAUAUCUGCCUCGAGAGAUCCUCAACCUUAUUCAUUUGGAAGAGUUGAGUUUACGAGGAAAUCCAUUGGUUGUUCGUUUUGUUAGAGAUUUAACCUAUGAUCCUCCAACUCUCCUGGAAUUAGCUGCACGGACCAUUAAGAUUCGAAAUAUUUCCUACACUCCCUAUGAUCUUCCUGGAAAUCUUCUUAGAUACUUGGGUUCAGCCAGCAAUUGCCCAAACCCAAAGUGUGGAGGAGUCUACUUUGACUGCUGUGUCAGACAAAUUAAAUUUGUGGACUUCUGUGGGAAGUAUCGCCUCCCACUGAUGCACUACUUGUGUUCACCAGAAUGUUCUUCCCCUUGCAGUUCUGCCUCUCACAGCUCCACUUCCCAGAGUGAAUCUGACUCAGAAGAUGAAGCUAGUGUUGCUGCACGCAGAAUGCAGAAAGUUCUUCUUGGUUGAACAGGAGUGCACAGUGUUGUGAAAUACUUAAAAAACUGAGCAAAAUGGUUAGACAAGAAAAUAGAGCUUGAAGUUCACUAGAAAUCUUAUCUUCAUCUUAAGUGUUCAUCAAAGAGUCUGGGAUGAUAUAAAACAUUUUGUGUUUCAUCUACCCAUUCAGCAAGAAUGAGUCCAGUCCCAUGUUUAGAUUAUUUUAACAUAAUUUGUGAAUGAUAGUUUCACAUUUGGCUGAUGGUUUGCAGUUUUCACUCAAGUUUUGCAUGAAUCACAAAGCAGAAUGGUACCUUUUGAAGAGCAGUUCUGCAAUAAGUCAUGAGUAGUAUAACUUUUGGACAUUGAGAUGGAGAAAGUGAGAAAUUAUCAAAGCUAUAAUUGCCAGAGUUGCCCUUGGGUUUAGGUAGAACACUGUAUACCAUAUAUACUAUAUACCAUAUAUACUAUAUAUACCAUAUAUAUUAUAUGCCAUAAACAGGAUUAACCCUCCCUUUUCUAAUUGCCUGUAUGUCUAGAUUACAGAACUAUUCAAAGAAGCUCACAGAUGGUUACAUGGGACAAACCUUUCUGACAAACUAACUGGUAAAGUAAGGCAUAUAACAUUUACAUGAGAUAUUAAAACUUUUUCAUUAUUAUCCUUUGUUCUAUAUGAUUGCUAUUAACCUUAUGUAAUCUAGCAAUGACUGUUAUAGUGCCUUAAUCCAGCAAGGAUAUAAAAAUGUAUUCAAGAAGUAAUGCCAGAGCAACCUAUAACCUGACAUACCAUGCAGAACAUUGUAAAAUAUUCUUUAACAGAACUAGGUAAAUAACUGUGUAUCUAAUAUCCGAUCUCAUGGCCCUCUUAACAUUUUUUUGUUUAAAUGUGCACUCAUCCCUUAUAAGCACAUUACUUUUACACUUAAUGGUAGGCCACAAUCUUCAUCAAUCUGUUCAUCAUAAGACAGAGUAAGAAUUUUUAACAGAAAAUUCUAAAAGAGAUAGAAGCUAGGAAAGCUUCUUUAUAUCUUGCAUUAAAUGGGUAGGGAAAAAAUAUGACUCUCACCCAUGUCAUGUACUGGACCAUCUUUCUCUACUUUUUAAAGAAAAACUAAUACAACUAGAAAAACAUCACAACAAGCCAAAUAAAAAUGGAGAAAAGGAGUCAUUGUCCUUAUACCUAAUGGAACAGUUUCCAGAACUACUUUAACUAUGGAAGCAUUUUUGAAAAUAAAGUAUUAAUAAAAUAGAAAAAAAUUAUUAAAUAUAUUGUAUCCUUAAUGUAUAGCAGGAAAAUAGUUUCACAAAUUAAUUGCUAUUAGAAAUUACCAAAUUUUUAUUAAGUACUUUAAUAUGCAAUACAAAUUGAAUAAUAGUACAACUAUAAGUUGAUAUAAAGUAAGUGCUUACUGGUAAUCAUUAAAUAACUAAUAACAUGACUUGUUGGUUAAUGUUAAACCUACAGUAAGAAAUGUUAUACAGAUCAGAUAGGCAUUAGAACAUCAGGUGUACCUUUUCUGAUUUCUGGCAUUCAUGGCACACCAUUUCUUAAAAGCAGAUUGUUGUAUAAUAACAUAUACAUGUAUUAGGGUUUUUUUCAUAUAUAUUUUUUAUUUUAGAAGAAACUAGCAUAAUUCAGGGUUUAUGUGUUUAUUUGUAUAUUAAUUCAUGAAACAUGAGAGUUUCAUGAACUGCAGAUGUGAAACGCUGCUAUAGAAUGAAUCCCUUCACCUUUACCUUGUUAUAAUGUAGUAAGAUUUUGUUUUCCUUUUGACUCAGAAAUUUUCUAUGUCUAUAGAGGUAAUCUAAUAUGUUCCUACUGCCUAGAAGAGUAAUACAUAGGUGAUUAUAUCAUAAAAUAGAGGUAUAAAGUCUUUGCUUACUUCUCCAUGUGGGCCACAGCAAGCUGCAGACUGUACAGUUAUGAAAGGUAAAGAUGACUUAGGCUGUGCCUAAGUGACAAAUGUAAAAUGUUUUGUAAAUAAGUGACUUACCUAAGAUACAUAAGAUAUUUUCAUAGAAAAUAAUGUAUUCAUAGUAAAAUACUCAAAUUGAUAGGACCAAUUUUUUCUGGCCUAAAUGCUUAUGCCUACUUCCUAAUCAAUUACCAGCUUGACUUAAGUAACUGCUUGAGUAGUCUUCUAAGAGUUAGUCUUCGUAAAAUAAAUGGAUAGGUAUGUAAAUAUAUAAUCUUACAUACCCUUUCCAGCUUCCUAGAAAGGUCUACUGCUUCAUCUUUUACAGAUGUAAAUAGGUCCAACCAGAGACAGUUUCUGGCCUUUGCAUAUAAGAAUAUAGAUGUAUACCACAGUAUUAUUUCAACAAAAUGUUAUGGUUCUAUGUAUAGUUGAAAACUCUAUGAUCAGCAUACAACUGUCUUUUGGUAAUUUUUAAUGAAGUCUACAUUUAGCCGUCGGUUUUAUCUUUCUUAAAUCUUUGACCUAAACUUUUGUAAGAGCAGCUAAUAAUUUCUAAGAUUUUCCCUGUUUCUUUUUCCUACCUUUCCUUUUCUCAUAACUGAUUGGAGAAAUUAAUCAGAAGUCAAAUACAAGGGACUUCAUAAUCUAGAAACCAGAUAAUCAGCUCCCAAGUCAUGUAGCUAACUAUGCAUUUAAAAUAAGUCUGUCUCUUUAGUUCUUAAGUCAUAUAUUUGUUUGUUAAUUACAGUAAAUGAACUUUAAUUGGGGUUUUUAAAAGACAGAAUUAGCGAAGUCUAAUUUUUAUAAUGAAAUAAGUUUUUGAUAUUGCUCUACUUGGACGAUUUUAGUGACCAAAACUAUGGAUAAAACUGCCUAAGCAUAACAUUAAUAUAUUUAGAAUGGCAUUCUUCAGUGCUAGUAUUUGAAAUUGGAAUUAGUACAUUGUGCAUUCUUAGUAGUCUUUAUCCCUAGAAUCAAUUCUCUCAGCAUCACCAAACUGAAUUGGUGAAAUAGUGCUAAGAUUCUGGGCAAUAGGAAGAUUAGUGAAUAUGAUACAUUGAUUCCAGGGUGCCAGGGAUUGGCUGACAUUAAGGACCAGCUGGCUAUGGUCCUCAGGCUACGGUCCUCAGUAUUCUAGUAUUUGAGUAGUGGAGGUAAAUCCAAAGGCGACUGGUUAUAUUUUACUUCUAAAUGUGUGCUGAAGUGUCUCUUGUUCAAAAAUUCUUGAUAUUUAGAGCUUCAAGUUACCACAUUUAAAAGUAAAGACUUGGCACGGUGGCACACACCUAUAAUCUUAGCACUUUGGGAGGCCGAAGUGGAUGGAUCAUAUGCAGUCAGGAAUUUGAGACCAGCCUGGCCAACAUGGUGAAACCUCAUCUUUACUAAAAAUACAAAAAUUAGCCGGGCGUUGUGACGCACACCCAUAGUCCCAGCUAACUCCGGAGGCUAAGACAAGAGAAUCACUUGAACUUGGGAGACAGAGGUUGCAGUAAUCUGAGAUCACUCCGCUGCACUCCAGCCUGAGUGAGAGUGAGACUGUGUCUCAAACAAACAAACAAAAAACAAACAAAAAAAUUUGCAUUGUAAAUUGUACCUCAAAUUUGAGCAGUUUUUGUGUUUGUGUAAAUUAAAGUAAAAAGCAGUCCACAAUAAUGUUUUGUAAUACUGCACACCAGUUCUACCAGAUUUUGUAACUAUCAGAUUUAAAUGAAAAAAGAGAAGGAAGAGGCUGAUUGCUGGAGUGUUAAAGAAAUCUUGGCCGGGCGUGGUGGCUCACGCUUGUAAUCCCAGCACUUUGGGAGGCCGAGGCGGGUGGAUCACGAGGUCAGGAGAUCGAGACCAUCCUGGCUAACACGGUGAAACCCCGUCUCUACUAAAAAUACAAAAAAAAAUUAGCCGGGCGUGAUGGCGGGCGCCUGUAGUCCCAGCUACUCGGGAGGCUGAGGCAAGAGAAUGGCGUGAACCCGGGAGGCGGAGCUUGCAGUGAGCCGAGAUUGCGCCACUGCACUCCCGCCUGGGCCACAGAGCGAGACUCCGUCUCAAAAAAAAAAAAAAAAAAAAAAGAAAUCUUUAGAAGCCACAGGGCUAGAAGAGAAGUCACCAAACACCUAGGGACAGUCCUAGGCCUAGAAAGCCCUUUAAAGUAAUAGUGAAUUGUUUUAAAAUUAAGUUAUUGAGUGGCCUACUGACUACCAUCCAAAAACCUUUAUCACCAAAUUUGUUCAGUGUUUGCUAUUGGGAGAUUGUCCAUAUCCCUCCGUAAUUAAGGGCCAGCAAGUAAUACGAUCUUCUUACAGCCAACCUUGCUCUUCCCAAAGGGAGAAAGUAAUACAUCAUUAACCUGGAAUUUGUGAUAUAACAGGUAGCCUUGGUUAAUGUUUACCUUUUCACUAUGUAAAAAAGAAAAAACACACAGCAAAUAGUGCAAAUAAAAUUUGGUCUUUUAAAGCAUUUUAGCAGUAGCUAUGUAAAAAAAGUUAAUGGUUAUUAUUCCUAAAUUUUCAUAAGACCCUUGGUAGACAAAACUAUCGGUUAUAUUAUGUAUAUAUGAGGUUAGUUAAGCUGCAUUUAGUUAGGAACAUUUAAUUUUUACCUAAAUGAUCCUUUUUUCAUCCAGAGGUAGAGAUUUUAUUGUCAUUAUGAAUGUUACUCCCCAUUUAGUCCAAAAUAGUGAGCUUUUAAGUUGUGCCAGGUACUUAACAAUAGUAAAAGCUAUUGUAUAGAUUUUUAUUCAAUGUGACCUAUAAUACAUUUCUGAUUCCUUCUGUAUUGAAUGUCCCAGUUUCCAUAUUAAGUGCUAUGCCCUGUAUAACAUUAAUGAAUUUAAUAGUGUACAAUUUUGGGCCAGGCAUGGUGGCUCACGCCAGUAAUCCUGGCACUUUGGGAGGCAGAGGCAGGCAGAUCACCUGAGGUCAGGGGUUCGAGAUCAGCCUGGCCAACAUGGCAAAAUCACAUCUCUACUAAAAAUACAAAAAUUAGCCAGGCGUGGUGGUGCAUGCCUGUAGUCCCAGCUACUCAGGAGGCUGAGGCAGGAGAAUCGCUUGAACCCAGGAGGCGGAGGUUGCAGUGAGCCGAGAUCAUGCCAUUGCACUCCAGCCUGGGAGACAGAGCAAGACUCUAUCUCAAAAAUAAAAAUAAAAAAAAAAUUGCGUGCAAUUUUGUAUUUUCAUAGUCGUAUCUUUUUAAAGGUAUCAUGAUUUCAGUUGUGGUCAGGAAGUAUGUGCCUUAAAUCCUCUACUCUAGACCCAAAGUUUGGAGAGCUAUAUUAUUUAAUAAGUUGUUUGUGACAGCCUUGUUACCUUUUUCAUUUGAUUUGAGGGAGAAAGACUGUGAUCCUGACAGAUUCCUUCUCAUAAAAUGGCCUAAUGUGUAUCAGUCUAGGACUUCUGGGGAGGGAACCUCUACCAUGCAUUCUGUCCCAGGAUGUCAAAGUCAUAAGAAUCAGGGUCCCCUGAAAUAAAAUCACUGAAAAGAUAUGUUCUGUUAUAUAUUAUUUAAAAAAUUUAUCUGGUGCCACCAAAGAAUGACAGCAGUUUCUAACCAACUUCAUAUUUAUAGCAUCUUAUGAAGAUAUUGUAAGGCUUAGCAUAUUUUGCCACUGGUUUUCUUUGUAAUAUAGGUUGAAAGUGAGACAUGUUUGAAUACUUUUGUAUGUAAAUAUCUCCCAUUCUUUUUCUAUCUCUUCUUGGUCUAUAUUUACUAAGAAUUGAUAUUUAAAAAACAGUUCACUAAUGAACUCUACAUAUUAUUGAACACUCACAGGGCAAUAUUGAUUUGGGUGCUACUAGACUUUUACCUAACAUUAGUCUUUCUCAAUAGUUGUUGUAAAGGAUAGUAUUCAAUCCAGUAAAUAUUAAAGUGUAUUAGUUUAAUGAAGGUUAUUUAUAUACUGUCAUACCACAAACCUAUGGUGGAAAGAACAUCUGCAUUCACCAGAAUGUACUUGUUCCUUUGGCUGUGAAUAAAUUGGAUAAGACUUUUUUAUUGUAAGUUCCAGCUGUUGGAAGAUACGGGGAUAAGAUUGACAUUGCUGUUGCAGUAUUGCAAAAACAUGACUAAAUUGGUUAAUUAUGUCUACCGCUUAUGUUUAAGAGAAUCCUUUCACUAACUUAAAUUGUUAACAUUGUUGUGAUAUUGAGAAAGAAUAUUAACCUAAACAGUCACUUUACAACAAUCAUGUAAAGACGUGUGCCUGCAGUUGAGGUUUUUUGCAUUUCUGAGCCUGCUUUGUAUUCAUGAGAAACAAAAACAUAAUGGGAGAAAAGUUUUAGAUAAGCAGCAUUGUAAGUUUUUGUAAAGUUUGGGAUGUCAAAGUAUUAACGAAGGGUACUGAAAACAUACUUUUACUUGGGUCAAAUUACUUUUUAUGAUCUGAUUUCUUAAUUUUCUGUAUUUGAAAUCUUGCAAAUUAGGAAUAUCUACAUCUAUAGAUAAAUAAGUAAAACUUAAUGGUAGAAAUAAGUGUAAUUCAGCAACAUGAUUCAACAAUUUUUAUAUUUAGGAUAAGUUAUUGUUUAUUAUAUUAAUAUCAAAUUUAUAUAUUGCCUUGUAAUGCUAAAUGCUCUUAAAAGAAUAUAUGGGCUACUUCAAUUCUACCACCUUCUUCCCCCUCCCCCAGGACGUACAAAAGAUCUUAUAUUAACCAAUCCUCUGUGAAUUUUGCCAUAUCAAACAUUGUGCCUUAUUUUAAUAAAACUGUUUUGUUGGAAUCCAGUUCUAUAUUAAAGUCUCUAUAAUGUUGAUAUUUGCCUGAUUACUUGUUACAUCAUUGAAUACAUACAUUAAAUAUGUACUAACAUUGA